CCCCAGGGCCCUGCUGCUGCCUUACCUUGCUGGGGUGACUGCUUGAUUAAAGACCCCAAGACUGGACCAGGCCCUGGUGUCCCCAGACCUGCAGCUAUGGCCCAACAAGGCAGGUGUUUGAGGAGGCCCUGCACAGGGUCCCAGGACUGCACCAGGGGCCUCAUCAGCAACCUGCUGAACUGGUGGUGUGAGGGGAGGGUGGGCUCCCUUGGUGGUAUCCUCCCUCUACCCCAGUGGGGGCUGGUGGGCCCUGAGAUGGAGGCAUCUCCUUGGGCCCUGCUGAGGAUGGCAGUAGUGGGUGAGCUCCUGGUGGGGGGAUGGGUGUGGGGCCGACUCCUCCAUCCCACAUGGGCUCCUGUGCCUCUCCCUAUCAGUUGGCCAGUGGAGCUCGAGAACAAACUGUUGCUGCCAGAUAAAGCAGCAAAGCCUGCUCCACUGCCCAGCGCAGGCCCCCUUCCCUUCCUCCACCAGGCUGAGUGGAGAACCCUAAAGCUACGGGACAGGCUCCCGUUCCCCGUGCCUACACAGGGUGCUGGCUCUGGCAGAAAGACAGUGUGCCCGCCCCGCAUCACCUGUCCGAGUGCGAACACCUUGGGAAGGGGGUUCCUGGUGGUCCUGUGACAACCAGAGACCCCCAGGGCCAAGGAGGCCACUGCAGCCCGGCCCUUCUGUGCCCUGGGCCCCUCCUCAUUGCAGCACCACCCACCGCACCACCCUGGGACAGAGGAAACACAUGGAGGCCAUAGCAUAGAGCCUGUCUGUUUAUAGAUCUCUGCCUGUCUUGUCCGUCCAUCCACUGUGUGUAUAUAUCUGUGUAUCUCUGUGGAGCGGGGAACGGGACAGUUGUGUAAAAAUCCAAAAUACAAUUCUGACUAUGAACAA